AAUCGCGUUUCCGGAGAGACCUGGCUGCUGUGUCCCGCGGCUUGCGCUCCGUAGUGGACUCCGCGGGCCUUCGGCAGAUGCAGGCCUGGGGUAGUCUCCUUUCUGGACUGAGAAGAGAAGAAUGGAGAAGCCCCUCUUCCCAUUAGUGCCUUUGCAUUGGUUUGGCUUUGGCUACACAGCACUGGUUGUUUCUGGUGGGAUCGUUGGCUAUGUAAAAACAGGCAGCGUGCCGUCCCUGGCUGCAGGGCUGCUCUUCGGCAGUCUAGCCGGCCUGGGUGCUUACCAGCUGUAUCAGGAUCCAAGGAACGUUUGGGGUUUCCUAGCCGCUACAUCUGUUACUUUUGUUGGUGUUAUGGGAAUGAGAUCCUACUACUAUGGAAAAUUCAUGCCUGUAGGUUUAAUUGCAGGUGCCAGAUGGAGUAUGGCUCUUGUUGCCCAAGCUGGGGUGCAAUGGUGCGAUCUCAGCUCAUUGCAACCUCCACCUCCCAGGUUCAAGCGAUUCUCCUGCCUUACCCUCCUGAGUAGCUGGGAUUUCAGGUGUGCACCACCACACCCAGCUAAUUUUUUGUAUUUUUAGUAGAGAUGGGGUUUCACCAUGUUGGCCAGGCUGGUCUUGAACUGACCUCAGGUGAUCCACCUGUCUUGCCUCCCAAAGUGCUGGAAUUACAGGCAUGAGCCACCGCACCAGGCCAAGAUCUAAUUCUUUUUAAUGGCUUUUAAGUUGUACGGAUGAUUACUAUUUAGUUUACUAUUCCCCUACUGAUAGAAAUAUGUCUUGUUUAAUGCCUUUGAUAGCCGGGAGCAGUGGCUCAUGCUUGUAAUCCCAACACUUUGGGAGGCUGAGGUGGGCAGAUCCCCUGAGGCCUUUGAUAUUACAAAGGAUGGUGUACCAAGAAAUAUCCUCAUGGAAAUCCCCGUGAACAUGUGCAAAGGAAUCUGUAGGUUACAUUCCUAAAUGCUGAGUCAGAGCAUCUCAGCAUUUAAAAUUGUGAUUGCCUUCAGAAGAGGAUGCACCAAUUUAUCCUCCCACUAGUGGUGGCUUUGUGUAAUUGGACUUUGUAAAAAUCUUUGACACAUUAAGCUGGAAGUCUGCAAACUUGUUCUGUAAAGGGCCAGAUAGUGAAUAUUUUAGGCUUCUCAGGCCAUCUGUGUCCCAGCUGUUCACCUCUGCCUUUGUAGAAUGAAAGCAGCCACAGCCAAUCAAUAAACGAGUGUGACUGUUCCAAUAAAACUAUGUAUGGGCCCUGAAA